AUACCCAUGGCCAACCUCCUACUCCUCAUUGUACCCAUUCUAAUCGCAAUGGCAUUCCUAAUGCUUACCGAACGAAAAAUUCUAGGCUAUAUACAACUACGCAAAGGCCCCAACGUUGUAGGCCCCUACGGGCUACUACAACCCUUCGCUGACGCCAUAAAACUCUUCACCAAAGAGCCCCUAAAACCCGCCACAUCUACCAUCACCCUCUACAUCACCGCCCCGACCUUAGCUCUCACCAUCGCUCUUCUACUAUGAACCCCCCUCCCCAUACCCAACCCCCUGGUCAACCUCAACCUAGGCCUCCUAUUUAUUCUAGCCACCUCUAGCCUAGCCGUUUACUCAAUCCUCUGAUCAGGGUGAGCAUCAAACUCAAACUACGCCCUGAUCGGCGCACUGCGAGCAGUAGCCCAAACAAUCUCAUAUGAAGUCACCCUAGCCAUCAUUCUACUAUCAACAUUACUAAUAAGUGGCUCCUUUAACCUCUCCACCCUUAUCACAACACAAGAACACCUCUGAUUACUCCUGCCAUCAUGACCCUUGGCCAUAAUAUGAUUUAUCUCCACACUAGCAGAGACCAACCGAACCCCCUUCGACCUUGCCGAAGGGGAGUCCGAACUAGUCUCAGGCUUCAACAUCGAAUACGCCGCAGGCCCCUUCGCCCUAUUCUUCAUAGCCGAAUACACAAACAUUAUUAUAAUAAACACCCUCACCACUACAAUCUUCCUAGGAACAACAUAUGACGCACUCUCCCCUGAACUCUACACAACAUAUUUUGUCACCAAGACCCUACUUCUAACCUCCCUGUUCUUAUGAAUUCGAACAGCAUACCCCCGAUUCCGCUACGACCAACUCAUACACCUCCUAUGAAAAAACUUCCUACCACUCACCCUAGCAUUACUUAUAUGAUAUGUCUCCAUACCCAUUACAAUCUCCAGCAUUCCCCCUCAAACCUA